GAUUUCCCAGCGCUGUCUCUGGGGAGCUCCGGCAGCGCAAGAGGGCAAAGCACAGCUGGAAGCUCAGAGCUGCAGUCCCAGGUCCUGGGCCAGGGCCCCCAUCCAGCAUCAAUGAAAGCAGAAGCCACAGUUAUUCCCAGCCGUUGUGCUAGGGGGCUCCCAUCAUGGCAAGUCCUCAGCCCAGUCCAGCCCUGGCAGACAAGUGCACCCCAGAACACGACCCAGCCCAAGCUCCUGGCUCCACACCAGCACGAGAAGUCCCAGAAGAAGAGCAGCCUUCUUAAGGAGCUGGGGGCCUUCCACAUCACCAUCGCUCUGCUGCACCUGGUCUUUGGGGGCUACCUGGCCUCUAUAGUCAAGAACCUUCACCUGGUGGUGCUGAAGUCUUGGUAUCCAUUCUGGGGGGCUGCCUCUUUUCUCAUUUCAGGGAUCUUGGCGAUAACAAUGAAGACCUUUUCUAAAACUUACCUGAAGAUGUUGUGCCUGAUGACAAACCUCAUCAGCCUCUUUUGCGUGCUGUCUGGCCUCUUCGUCAUCUCCAAGGAUCUCUUUCUGGAGAGCCCAUUUGAGUCCCCGAUCUGGAGAAUGUACCCCAACUCCACGGUCCACAUCCAGAGGCUGGAGCUGGCCUUGCUCUGCUUCACUGUCCUAGAGCUCUUCCUGCCAGUGCCCACAGCUGUCACAGCCUGGAGAGGGGACUGCCCAUCUGCAAAGAAUGAUGAUGCAUGCCUUGUUCCGAAUACACCAUUGCAUCUCAAAGGCCUGCCGGUGGAGCCCCCGCCAUCCUACCAGAGUGUGAUUCAAGGCGACGCACAACACAAGCAACAUCAGAGCUCUGCCCCAGCCACCAUGGCUUCCUUGAGGUUCCACAGACACCCCAGGGACACCCCUGCCUCUGAGCCAUCACCCUUGCCCUUCCUCCACCUGGAUUCUCUUCCCCCAGGCUCAGAGAAGUUAAGCAAGUUGCCCCGGACACAUGGAUAGUCACUGACGGAGCUGCGAUCUGGACCCAGACUGCAAACUGAAGAGCCACUGCCUGACAAUGCCCAAACUUGGUUGGAGCAUAGCCCCUGCUCUCCCAAAGUUGCACUUUCACUGGGAAGAUGAGAUUUGCACAUACAAAAGGCUAGAGCGAUGGUCUAUACAGCAAAGUCAGCCCUCACAGCUCCUGGGAACGCUGUCCUCUCAGAUAAGCCAUUUCUUACAUAGUUGAUGGCUCGAUAUCUGUGGUGGCCCAGAUUGUUUUGUUUUGUUUCGCUUUGUUUUGUUUUCUUUUGUUUUGUUGAGAUGGAGUCUCGCUCUGUUGCCCAGCCCAGAGUACAGUGGCACUAUCUCAGCUCACUGCAAUCUCCGCCUCCCUGGUUCAAGUGAUUCUCCUAUCUCAGCCUCCCAAGUAGCUGGGACUAUAGGCACACGCCACCACGCCCAGCUAAUUUUUAUAUUUUUAGUAGAGACAGGAUUGCACCAUAUUGGUCAGCCUGGUCUCAAACUCCUGACCUCAGGUGAUCCACCUGCCUCAGCCUCCCAAAGUGCUGGGAUUACAGGCGUGAGCCACUGUGCCCAGCCCAGGUUUUGAAGUUGUCCGAGAUAGCAGUCUGCUCUCUACUGCCUUAUAAAAUCCCUGUGUGAAGGGAUGCUCUCAGUAUCAUUUGCCCUUGCACAGAAUAUCCCUGGGGUUUGAGGUUCUUUGAAUUCUCCCUCUUUGUCAUCUCUUUCGCUGCCACUUCUGGCUGUGGUCACUAGCUUGGCCAUAGCACCUCUCUUCUCCACUUCUGAUCUGCUGCUUCUAACCUUCUAUAGAUUGCAGCUGGCUUUAAAAUAGAUUGUAAAGUGUAAGGCAUUAGGUUCUGAGACAGCGGCAGAGAGAGCCAUGCAAAUGUUUAGGACAACCCAGUCUUUCUUUUUUUUUUUUUUUUUUUUUUUUUUUGAGACGGAGUCUCACUCUGUCACCCAGGCUGGAGUGCUGUGGUGCAAUCUCGGCUCACUGCAACCUCUGCCUCCCGAGUUCAAGCAAUUCUCCUGCCUCAGCCUCCCGAGUAGCUGGGAUUACAGGCGACCGCCACCACGCCUGGCUACUUUUUGUAUUUUUAGUAGAGACAGGGUUUCACCACGUUAGCCAUGAUGGUCUCAAACUUCUGACCUCAUAAUCCACCCACCUUGGCCUCCCAAAGUGCUAGGAUUACAGGCAUGAGCCACCACCCCUGGCUGAAACCCAAUCUUUCAAAACAUGAAAGGGGGUGAUGGAGAAAACCUUAGCUUGGUUGUCUAAAGACAUGGGUGCAAACUCUAGGCUAGCUCUGCCAAUCACUUACUGUGCGGGUUUGACUCAGUCCCUUCCCCUCACUAGGUCCCAGUUUCUCCAUUUGUAAAACAAGCAAUUGUGCUACAUUGAUGGUUUACAUCAAUAAAGGUUGAAACGGC